GUCACUGAGCCGCGCCAGCUGAGCCAGGUAGGGCCCUACCCUCUUCUGUUGCUUUCUCCCUGUGGCUCGCGCCGUCCCCCGCCGCCCGUCGACCCCGCUUCCAUGUCCCUGGCGGACACAGCUCCCAGGAACCUCCACGCCCAUGGCCACUAGGCAGAGGGAAUCCUCUAUCACCUCCUGCUGUUCCACCUCGAGCUGCGACGCAGACGACGAGGGCGUGCGCGGCACCUGCGAAGAUGCUUCCCUGUGCAAGAGAACUGCCAUCAGCAGCGCCCGACAGCACUCUCCUCCUCACUGCCCAACACUGGGUGGCAAAUCUUUUCAUCUUGGCCACUCUGAUAGGCUGGACAGUGAGGUCCUUCUUCCUAGGGCGCAUGGAAACCUGUUGCAGUCACCUGGGUUUGCGGAGUGGGAGGAGGUUUGCAGUAAGCAUUGGCUACUGGCAUGACCCUUACAUACAGCACUUUGUGAGACUGUCUAAAGAGAGGAAAGCCCCUGAAAUCAACAGAGGAUAUUUUGCUCGAGUCCAUGGUGUCAGUCAGCUUAUAAAGGCAUUUCUACGGAAGACAGAAUGUCAUUGUCAAAUUGUCAACCUUGGGGCAGGCAUGGAUACCACCUUCUGGAGAUUAAAGGAUGAAGAUCUUCUCCCAAGUAAAUAUUUUGAGGUUGACUUUCCAAUGAUUGUCACGAGAAAGCUGCACAGUAUCAAAUGCAAGCCUCCCCUAUCCAGCCCCAUUCUAGAACUGCAUUCAGAGGACACACUUCAGAUGGAUGGACACAUACUGGAUUCAAAGAGAUAUGCCGUUAUUGGAGCAGAUCUCCGAGACCUGUCUGAACUGGAAGAGAAGCUAAAGAAAUGUAACAUGAAUACACAAUUGCCAACACUCCUGAUAGCUGAAUGUGUGCUGGUUUACAUGACUCCAGAGCAGUCCGCAAACCUCCUGAAGUGGGCAGCCAACAGUUUUGAGAGAGCCAUGUUCAUAAACUACGAACAGGUGAACAUGGGUGAUCGGUUUGGGCAGAUCAUGAUUGAAAACCUGCGGAGACGCCAGUGUGACCUGGCGGGAGUGGAGACCUGCAAGUCAUUAGAGUCACAGAAAGAACGGCUCCUGUCGAAUGGGUGGGAAACAGCAUCGGCCGUCGACAUGAUGGAGUUGUACAACAGGUUACCUCGAGCUGAAGUGAGCAGGAUAGAAUCACUUGAAUUCCUGGAUGAAAUGGAGCUGCUGGAGCAGCUCAUGCGGCAUUACUGCCUUUGCUGGGCAACCAAAGGAGGAAAUGAGCUUGGGCUGAAGGAGAUAACUUAUUAAUCUGUCGAAGGCUUAUGCCGAGCCAGAAGCCGAAGCCACUUGCCCUCCUGGAGGAGACCUGCAAGCUCCCUGAGCGGUGGGCGGGCCUCGUCCGCAGGUCUCAUCCCACACUCUUGAGAAGCCUUGGUCACUACAGUGGUCGCACAUGUUCCUCUUCCUGUUCCUGUUGACAUGUCGUUGUUUAAAUAAAUCUCACUUGCCACCA